GUCUCUCCCUGCAGCUGGAGCUCCAGGUCGUCUGUUCACUGCUCUCUGUCUUCUUCUCCUAGAGGCCCAGCCUCUGUGGCCCUGUGUCCUGCAGGUAUUGGGAGAUCCACAGCUAAGACGCCAGGACCCCCUGGAAGCCUAGAAAUGGUGAGAGUGCCGGUCCAGCAUCCCGAGAGAGGGGCCAUUGCAAUUUAGAGAUGUGGCCAUAGAAUUCUCUCUGGAGGAGUGGCAUUGCCUGGACAUGGCACAGCGGAAUUUAUAUAGGGAUGUGAUGUUAGAGAACUACAGAAACCUGGUCUUUCUUGGUAUUGUUGUCUCAAAGCCAGACCUCAUCACCCAUCUGGAGCAAGGAAAAAAACCUUCGACUAUGCAGAGACAUGAGAUGGUAGCCAACCCCUCAGUUUUGUGUUCUCAUUUUAACCAAGACCUUUGGCCAGAGCAGAGCAUAAAAGAUUCUUUCCAAAAACUGAUACUGAGAAGGCAUAAAAAAUGUGGACAUGAUAAUUUGCAGUUAAAAAAAGGCUGUGAAAGUGUGGAUAAGUGUAAAGUGCACAAAAGAGGUUAUAAUGGACUUAACCAAUGUUUGACAACUACCCAAAGCAAAAUGUUUCAAUGUGAUAAACAUGGGAAAGUCUUUCAUCAAUUUUCAAAUACAAACAGACAUAAGAUAAGACAUACUGGAAAAAACCCUUGCAAAUUUACAGAAUGUGGCAAAGCUUUUAACCGGUCCUCAACCUUUACUACACAUAAGAAAAUUCAUACUGGAGAGAAACCCUAUAAAUGUAUAGAAUGUGGCAAAGCCUUCAACCGGUCCUCACACCUUACUACACAUAAGAUAAUUCAUACUGGAGAGAAACGGUACAAAUGUGAAGACUGUGGCAAAGCCUUUAACCGCUCCUCUAACCUUACUACACAUAAGAAAAUUCAUACUGGAGAGAAACCCUACAAAUGUGAAGAAUGUGGCAAGGCCUUUAAGCGCUCCUCUAUCCUUACUACACAUAAGAGAAUUCAUACUGGAGAGAAACCCUACAAAUGUGAAGAAUGUGGCAAAGUUUUUAAGUACCUUUCUUCCCUUUCUACACAUAAGAUAAUUCAUACUGGAGAGAAACCCUACAAAUGUGAAGAAUGUGGUAAAGCCUUCAACUGGUCCUCACACCUUACUACACAUAAGAGAAUUCAUACUGGAGAGAAACCCUACAAAUGUGAAGAAUGUGGCAAAGGCUUUAAGUACUCCUCUACCCUUACUAAACAUAAAAUAAUCCAUACUGGAGAGAAACCCUACAAAUGUGAAGAAUGUGGUGAAGCCUUUAAGUACUCCUGUUCCCUUACUGCACAUAAGAUAAUUCAUACUGGAAAGAAACCUUACAAAUGUGAAGAAUGUGGCAAAGUGUUUAAGCACUCCUCUCCCCUUUCUAAACAUAAGAGAAUUCAUACUGGAGAGAAACCCUACAAAUGUGAAGAAUGUGGCAAAGCCUUCAGUCGGUCCUCUAUUCUUACUACACAUAAGAUAAUUCACACUGGAGAGAAACCCUACGAAUGUGAAGACUGUGGCAAAGCCUUUAACCGCUCCUCUAACCUUACUAAACACAAGAAAAUUCAUACUGGAGAGAAGCCUUACAAAUGUGAAGAAUGUGGCAAGGCCUUUAAGUGCUCCUCUAUUCUUACUACACAUAAGAGAAUUCAUACUGCAGAUAAACCCUACAAAUGUGAAGAAUGUGGCAAAGACUUUAAGUACUCCUCUACCCUUACUAGACAUAAGAAAAUUCAUACUGGAGGGAAACCACACAAGUGCAAUAAAUGUGGCAAAGCCUUUAUUUCAUCCUCAAACCUUAGUAGACAUGAGAUAAUUCAUAUGGGAGGGAAUCCCUACAAAUGUGAAAAUGUGGCAAAGCCUUAGACACUCCUCUACCCUUACUAGACAUAAGAUAAUUCAUACUGGAGAGAAACCCUAUGAGUUUGAUGAAUGUGGGAAAGACUUUAACCAGCUAUCAACUUUUACUAAAUAUGAGAAUUUAUGGAACACAAACACUACAAAUAUAAAGAAUGUGACAAAGCUUUUAGGAAGUUCUCAACCCUUAUUACACAUAAUUCAUACUGGAUAGAAACCCUACACCUGUGAAGAAUGUGGCAUAGCCUAUAACAAUUUUCAAUCAAUUCUUUUUUUUUUUUUUUGAGAUGAAGUUUCAUGCUUGUCACCCAAGCUGGAAUACAAUGUGAUGAUCUCGGAUCACUGAAACCUCUGCCUCCCGGGUUCAAGCCAUUUUCCUGCCUCAGCUUGUCUAGUAGAUGAGAUUAUGGGGGGUGGAGCCAAGAUGGCUGAAUAGGUACAGCUCCUGUCUACAGCUCCCAGCCUGAGCGACGCAGAAGAUGGGUGAUUUCUGCAUUUCCGUCUGAUGUACCAGGUUCAUCUCACUAGGGAGUGCCAGACAGUGGCUGCAGGACAGUGGGUGCAGUGCACUGUGCAUGAGCUGAAGCAGGGCGAGGCAUUGCCUCACUCACGAAGCGCAAGGAGUCAGGGAGUUCCCUUUCCUAGUCAAAGAAAGGGGUGACAGAUGGCACCUGGAAAAUUGGGUUACUCCCACCCUAAUACUGCGCAAUUCCAAUGGGCUUAAAAAAUGGCACACCAGAUUAUAUCCUGCAGCUGGCUCAGAGGGUCCUAUGCCCAUGGAGUCUCACUGAUUGCUAGCACAGCAGUCUGAGAUCAAACUGCAAGGCAGCAGCGAGGCUGGGGGAGGAGCGCCUGCCAUUGCCCAGGCUUGCUUAGGUAAAGCAGCUGGGAAGCUAGAACUGGGUGGAGCCCACCACAGCUCAAGGAGGCCUGCCUGCCUCUGUAGGCUCCACCUCUGGGGUCAGGGCACAGACAAAAAGACAGCAGUAACCUCUGCAGACUUAAACGUCCCUGUCUGACAGCUUUGAAGAGAGUAGUGGUUCUCCCAGCACGCAGCUGGAGAUCUGAGAACGGGCAGACUGCCUCCUCAAGUGGGUCUCUGACCCCCGAGCAGCCUAACUGGGAGGCACACCCCAGUAGGGGCAGACUGACACUUCACACGGCUGGGUACUCCUCAUAUAAAACUUCCAGAGGACCGAUCAGGCAGCAGCAUUUGUGGUUCAUGAAAAUCCGCUGUUCUACAGCCACUGAUGCUGAUACCCAGGCAAACAGCGUCUGGAGUGGACCUCUAGCAAACUCCAACAGACCUGCAGCUGAGGGUCCUGUCUGUUAGAAGGAAAACUAACAAACAGAAAGGACAUCCACACCAAAAACCCAUCUGUACAUCACCAUCAUCAAAGACCAAAAGUAGAUAAAACCACAAAGAUGGGGAAAAAACAGAGCAGAAAAACUGGAAAGUCUAAAAAGCAGAGCACCUCUCCUCCUCCAAAGGAACACAGUUCCCCACCAGCAACAGAACAAAGCUGGAUGGAGAAUGACUUUGAUGAGUUGAGAGAAGAAGGCUUCAGACGAUCAAACUACUCCGAGCUACAGGAGGAAAUUCAAACCAAAGGCAAAGAAGUUAAAAAAUUAGACGAAUGUAUAACUAGAAUAACCAAUGCAGAGAAAUGCUUAAAGGAGCUGAUGGAGCUGAAAGCCAAGGAUCAAGAACUACGUGAAGAAUGCAGAAGCCUCAGGAGCCAAUGCGAUCAACUGGAAGAAAGGGUAUCAGUGAUGGAAGAUGAAAUGAAUGAAAUGAAGUGAGAAGGGAAGUUUAGAGAAAAAAAAUUAAAAAGAAACAAAGUCUCCAAGAAAUAUGGGACUAUGUGAAAAGACCAAAUCUACCUCUGAUUGGUGUACCUGAAAGUGAGGGGGAGAAUGGAACCAACUUGGAAAACACUCUGCAGGAUAUUAUCCAGGAGAACUUCCCCAAUCUAGCAAGGCAGGCCAACAUUCAGAUUCAGGAAAUACAGAGAACGCCACAAAGAUACUCCUUGAGAAGAGCAACUCCAAGACACAUAAUUGUCAGAUUCACCAAAGUUGAAAUGAAGGAAAAAAUGUUAAGGGCAGCCAGAGAGAAAGGUCGGGUUACCCACAAAGGGAAGCCCAUCAGACUCACAGCUGACCUCUUGGCAGAAACUCUAUAAGCCAGAAGAGAGUGGGGGCCAAUAUUCAACAUUCUUAAAGAAAAGAAUUUUCAACCCAGAAUUUCAUAUCCAGCCAAACUAAGCUUCAUAAGUGAAGGAGAAAUAAAAUACUUUACAGACAAGCAAAUGCUGAGAGAUUUUGUCACCACCAGGCCUGCCCUAAAAGAGCUCCUGAAGGAAGCACUAAACAUGGAAAGGAACAACUGAUACCAGCCGCUGCAAAAUCAUGCCAAAAUGUAAAGACCAUCGAGACUAGGAAGAAACUGCAUGAACUAACGAGCAAAAUAACCAGCUAACAUCAUAAUGACAGCAUCAAAUUCUCACAUAACAAUAUUAGCUUUAAAUGUAAAUGGGCUAAAUGCUCCAAUUAAAAGACACAGACAGGCAAAUUGGAUAAAUAGUCAAGACCCAUCAGGGUGCUGUAUUCAGGAAACCCAUCUCACGUGCAGAGACACACAUAGGCUCAAAAUAAAAGGAUGGAGGAAGAUCUACGAAG